AGAGCGCCGCCGCCGCCGCUGCUGCAGCAGCAGCUGCUCUGCAGAGUGGUGGCCGGGGCCAGGGCCGGGGUGCCCUCCCUCCCACCUUCUCCCGCCAUGAGCCAGGGAAGUCCGGGGGACUGGGCCCCCCUAGAUCCCACCCCCGGACCCCCAGCAUCCCCCAACCCCUUCGUGCAUGAGUUACAUCUCUCUCGCCUCCAGAGGGUUAAGUUCUGCCUCCUGGGGGCAUUGCUGGCCCCCAUCCGAGUGCUUCUGGCCUUUAUCGUCCUCUUUCUCCUCUGGCCCUUUGCCUGGCUUCAAGUGGCCGGUCUUAGUGAGGAGCAGCUUCAGGAGCCAAUUACAGGAUGGAGGAAGACUGUGUGCCACAACGGGGUGCUAGGCCUGAGCCGCCUGCUGUUUUUCCUGCUGGGCUUCCUCCGGAUUCGCGUUCGUGGCCAGCGAGCCUCUCGCCUUCAAGCCCCUGUCCUUGUUGCUGCCCCACACUCCACUUUCUUUGACCCCAUUGUUCUGCUGCCCUGUGACCUGCCCAAAGUUGUGUCCCGAGCUGAGAACCUUUCCGUUCCUGUCAUUGGAGCCCUUCUUCGAUUCAACCAAGCCAUCCUGGUAUCCCGGCAUGACCCGGCUUCUCGACGCAGAGUGGUGGAGGAGGUCCGAAGGCGGGCCACCUCAGGAGGCAAGUGGCCGCAGGUGCUAUUCUUUCCUGAGGGCACCUGUUCCAACAAGAAGGCUUUGCUUAAGUUCAAACCAGGAGCCUUCAUCGCAGGGGUGCCUGUGCAGCCUGUCCUCAUCCGCUACCCCAACAGUCUGGACACCACCAGCUGGGCAUGGAGGGGUCCUGGAGUACUCAAAGUCCUCUGGCUCACAGCCUCUCAGCCCUGCAGCAUUGUGGAUGUGGAGUUCCUUCCUGUGUAUCACCCCAGCCCUGAGGAGAGCAGGGACCCCACCCUCUAUGCCAACAAUGUUCAGAGGGUCAUGGCACAGGCUCUGGGCAUUCCAGCCACCGAAUGUGAGUUUGUAGGGAGCUUACCUGUGAUUGUGGUGGGCCGGCUGAAGGUGGCGUUGGAACCACAGCUCUGGGAACUGGGAAAAGUGCUUCGGAAGGCUGGGCUGUCCGCUGGCUAUGUGGACGCUGGGGCAGAGCCAGGCCGGAGUCGAAUGAUCAGCCAGGAAGAGUUUGCCAGGCAGCUACAGCUCUCUGAUCCUCAGACGGUGGCUGGUGCCUUUGGCUACUUCCAGCAGGAUACCAAGGGUUUGGUGGACUUCCGAGAUGUGGCCCUUGCACUAGCAGCUCUGGAUGGGGGCAGGAGCCUGGAAGAGCUAACUCGUCUGGCCUUUGAGCUCUUUGCUGAAGAGCAAGCAGAGGGUCCCAACCGCCUGCUGUACAAAGACGGCUUCAGCACCAUCCUGCACCUGCUGCUGGGUUCACCCCACCCUGCUGCCACAGCUUUGCAUGCUGAGCUGUGCCAGGCAGGAUCCAGCCAAGGCCUCUCCCUCUGUCAGUUCCAGAACUUCUCCCUCCAUGACCCACUCUAUGGGAAACUCUUCAGCACCUACCUGCGCCCCCCACACACCUCUCGAGGCACCUCCCAGACACCAAAUGCCUCAUCCCCAGGCAACCCCACUGCUCUGGCCAAUGGGACUGUGCAAGCACCCAAGCAGAAGGGAGACUGAGUGCCUCAGCCUCUCACCCCCUCCUCCUCAGGGCAGCGCUAGGGGCCUCCCCUAUGCCUCAGCCCCAUCUCUGCUCCUGUUUGAAUUUUGUUAUUGUUGUUUGGUUGUUGUUUUUUUAAGUUGAUUUUAAUUUUUUGUUUGGUUGAUUUUUUUGUAAAAAACUAUUUUAUAUAUAAAUAUAAAUCUAUAUCUAUAUCUAUUAAAAAAAAUGAAGUCCAGUCAUAUUGAUGUUACCAUUACUUGGGAAGGAAAGGGAUGAAUGGUUGUAGGACGCCCGUUGGAAAAUCACAAAUGUUUCCAAGGUUCGUCCUCUUGGCCAUAGCUGGAUGAAUCUUCCUCUUCGGACAGGGCUCUUUCCUGCACAGAAAUCAUACUGAGGUUCCAUAUCCUCCCUCCUGCUGUCAUCUCCUAUAUGUACAUUUUAACAGACUUCCUCGUGAACCUCUUUUCAGCCCAUUCCCUCUUGCUCUGUCCUCAUUAAAGAUUAAAAAAUA